AGUAAAAUUACCAAGCAGGCAUUGAUGCUAAUGUGAACCAGAAAAAAAGCUCCUUAAUUAUACUCAUUAGGCCUGUAGCUGAUCCAGCCCAUACAGAAGAGGCACAAUGACCACUGUUCUGGGGAGCGAAGUAAUCUUGGCAGAAAACCUCACCAUGGUCACCGAAUUCCUGUUGCUGGGUUUUUCCAGCCUUGGUGAAAUUCAGCUGGCCCUCUUUGUAGUUUUUCUUUUUCUGUAUCUAGUCAUUCUUAGUGGCAAUGUCACCAUUAUCAGUGUCAUCCACCUGGAUAAAAGCCUCCACACACCAAUGUACUUCUUCCUUGGCAUUCUCUCAACAUCUGAGACCUUCUACACCUUUGUCAUUCUACCCAAGAUGCUCAUCAAUCUACUUUCUGUGGCCAGGACAAUCUCCUUCAACUGUUGUGCUCUUCAAAUGUUCUUCUUCCUUGGUUUUGCCAUUACCAACUGCCUGCUAUUGGGUGUGAUGGGUUAUGAUCGCUAUGCUGCCAUUUGUCACCCUCUGCAUUACCCCACUCUUAUGAGCUGGCAGGUGUGUGGAAAACUGGCAGCUGCCUGUGCAAUUGGUGGCUUCUUGGCCUCUCUUACAGUAGUAAAUUUAGUUUUCAGCCUCCCUUUUUGUAGCGCCAACAAAGUCAAUCAUUACUUCUGUGACAUCUCAGCAGUCAUUCUUCUGGCUUGUACCAACACAGAUGUUAACGAAUUUGUGAUAUUCAUUUGUGGAGUUCUUGUACUUGUGGUUCCCUUUCUGUUUAUCUGUGUUUCUUAUCUCUGCAUUCUGAGGACUAUCCUGAAGAUUCCCUCAGCUGAGGGCAGACGGAAAGCGUUUUCCACCUGCGCCUCUCACCUCAGUGUUGUUAUUGUUCAUUAUGGCUGUGCUUCCUUCAUCUACCUGAGGCCUACAGCAAACUAUGUGUCCAACAAAGACAGGCUGGUGACGGUGACAUACACGAUUGUCACUCCAUUACUAAACCCCAUGGUUUAUAGCCUCAGAAACAAGGAUGUCCAACUUGCUAUCAGAAAAGUGUUGGGCAAGAAAGGUUCUCUAAAACUAUAUAAUUGAAAUAUUAUUACAUUUUAGAUUUCUUAAUAAAUAAUGCCUUUUUAUCACAAG